AGAAGGGGCCAGCCCGCGCCUUUCGCGCUUCUGCCCUGGCCCUCUGCGGGCCGCUCCGCCGGUGCUGUCCCUGGGCGCCUCCGUGCUCUCAGCCAACCACCUCUGAGAGCGCCCACUCGAGCGCCCCGGGAGCCAGAGGGCGGGGGUCCUCGCCGGGACCCUCCUGUGGGCCCAGGGGUGAGUGUUGACGUCUUCCCGACCCGCGACCUGCCGCCCGAGCUGGCUGCCAGGCCUAUCGCCGCCGCCGAGACCCUCCGGCCAACAGGGACCCGCGGUGGCCCCGGCCCCCCCGGGACAAAAGUGGCUCUCAAUCCAGCACAUGCACAUUGAAGCAAGUUAAAGGAUUUAAUAUGAAGCACAGAAGCAGAUAGUGCCAAAUAGCAAGCAGUAGUUGUUACACAUUUCUGGAAAAGCAGUGUCCGUGUUGUUAUGUACACCUCCAAAAAAAGUUCAAAUGUGUAGGGGAAUUGUUGUGUAAAGUAAACUGAACUGCAGGGUAGCAGUAUUUUAAUAGCUAUUAUAGACCUGUAUUUACUGUAUUUAAAUGAGUAAAGGAACAAGCAGUGACACAUCACUAGGAAGGGUGAGCAGGGCAGCAUUUCCUUCUCCCACUGCUGCUGAGAUGGCAGAAAUUAGUCGAAUUCAGUACGAAAUGGAAUAUACUGAAGGCAUUAGUCAGCGAAUGAGGGUCCCAGAAAAGUUAAAAGUAGCACCGCCAAACGCUGACCUGGAACAAGGAUUCCAAGAAGGAGUUCCAAAUGCUAGUGUGAUAAUGCAAGUUCCGGAGAGGAUUGUUGUAGCAGGAAAUAAUGAAGAUGUUUCAUUUUCAAGACCAGCAGAUCUUGACCUUAUUCAGUCAACUCCCUUUAAACCCCUGGCACUGAAAACACCACCUCGUGUACUUACGCUGAGUGAAAGACCACUAGAUUUUCUGGAUUUAGAAAGACCUCCUACAACCCCUCAAAAUGAAGAAAUCCGAGCAGUUGGCAGACUAAAAAGAGAGCGGUCUAUGAGUGAAAAUGCUGUUCGCCAAAAUGGACAGCUGGUCAGAAAUGAUUCUCUUGUGACACCAUCGCCACAACAGGCUCGGGUCUGUCCUCCCCAUAUGUUACCUGAAGAUGGAGCUAAUCUUUCCUCUGCUCGUGGCAUUUUGUCGCUUAUCCAGUCUUCUACUCGUAGGGCAUACCAGCAGAUCUUGGAUGUGCUGGAUGAAAAUCGCAGACCUGUGUUGCGUGGUGGGUCUGCUGCCGCCACUUCUAAUCCUCAUCAUGACAACGUCAGGUAUGGCAUUUCAAAUAUAGAUACAACCAUUGAAGGAACGUCAGAUGACCUGACUGUUGUAGAUGCAGCUUCACUAAGACGACAGAUAAUCAAACUAAAUAGACGUCUACAACUUCUGGAAGAGGAGAACAAAGAACGUGCUAAAAGAGAAAUGGUCAUGUAUUCAAUUACUGUAGCUUUCUGGCUGCUUAAUAGCUGGCUCUGGUUUCGCCGCUAGAGGUAACAUCAGCCCUCAAAAAUACUGUCUCAACAGCUGGAAAUAUAAAAGAUUUGCAAACUUCUUUGUUUCUGUCUCUGCAUUGUAUGCCAUUUUAUAGUCCACACCCUGAAAAUGUAUUUCUUCCAGAAAGUCUGGAGGAAGGACCUAUAUUUGUAGAAGUAAAGGUAUAUUCUGUCACUCAGCUGUAUUCACGUCUGAGCAGUUCUGCAGUAACACCUGCUUAAAAUUCUCCCUUUGCAUGUUUUGUAAAUAGGCUCCAGUUUUGUUUUUUAAAAGGAAUUUAUUUUUUGCCUCAUCAGUCCACCCAACUGAUUCUGAAUGGGAGAGAGUCUGUAGAGAAUUGAUUCAGAAAAGUGUCUGUGAAAGAAAAACAAUUAUUUUGUCCUGUUUCUCAAACAGUGUUAAGCAGUUUUGUUAAUAGACAUUUUUGCAUCGACACUUCAACAUUAACACUUUCAAAGUCAUGGUCUGGUGCCAGAUUUAAGAAACUCGAACCACCUAAUAUUUCAUAACCUUCUUCAUUAGGUACUUGUACAGAUUAAUUUCUAACAUUGCAGCAGUUUCAUAUGUGUGCAAUAUGUGCAUUCUUUCAUUUUAGUUUUGCACUUGGUUUUCUAUAAAGUACGUUUUUACUCAGUUCAUGCGUGAACAAUUUAAAAAACGACAGAAUAAGGUACAAAUGUAGUGUAUUUAAUAAACUGUCAACCAAAGAAGUA